GCUGCUAUGGAGGCGCUGGCCAUGGGUUCCCGGGCGCUGCGGCUCUGGCUGGUCGCACCCGGUGGCGGGAUCAAAUGGAGAUUUAUAGCAACAUCGUCAGCUUCUCAGCUGUCACCGACAGAAUUGACAGAAAUGCGGAAUGAUCUCUUUAAUAAAGAGAAAGCCAGGCAGUUAUCAUUAACUCCCCGAACUGAGAAGAUAGAAGUUAAGCAUGUUGGGAAAACUGACCCCGGUACUGUCUUCGUGAUGAAUAAAAACAUUUCAACUCCCUACAGUUGUGCCAUGCAUUUAAGCGAGUGGUAUUGCAGGAAGUCCAUUCUGGCUCUGGUGGAUGGACAGCCUUGGGACAUGUAUAAGCCUUUAACAAAGUCCUGUGAAAUUAAAUUUCUUACUUUCAAAGAUUGUGAUCCAGGAGAAGUGAAUAAGGCAUAUUGGCGUUCCUGUGCUAUGAUGAUGGGCUGUGUGAUAGAGAGGGCAUUCAAAGAUGAAUAUAUGGUCAAUUUGGUCAGAGCUCCAGAAGUUCCUGUAAUUUCUGGUGCCUUCUGUUAUGACGUAGUUUUGGAUAGCAAACUUGAUGAGUGGAUGCCAACAAAAGAGAACUUACGUUCCUUCACAAAAGAUGCUCAUGCUUUAAUUUAUAAAGAUCUUCCAUUUGAAACUCUGGAAGUUGAAGCAAAAGUGGCAUUGGAAAUAUUUCAACACAGCAAGUACAAAGUAGAUUUCAUAGAAGAGAAGGCAUCUCAGAACCCUGAGAGAAUAGUCAAGCUACACAGAAUAGGUGACUUCAUUGAUGUGAGUGAGGGCCCUCUUAUUCCAAGAACAAGUAUUUGUUUCCAGUAUGAAGUAUCAGCAGUUCACAAUCUUCAACCCACCCAGCCAAGUCUCAUACGAAGAUUCCAGGGCGUGUCUUUACCUGUUCACUUAAGAGCACAUUUUACAAUAUGGGAUAAGCUAUUGGAAAGAUCUCGGAAAAUGACUCCAUUUCCCAUUCUCCUUCUAUUUACUACGCAGUCAUUCUUCACUACCUCGCCUGAGUCGUACCUCCUCCAUGGAACAGUCUCAGAGUAACUGAAGAUCAAAGUAAAGCAACAGAGGAAUGUACAUCUACCUAAUAACUUUCUAAAAUUUAAAUAUGUAUAAUAAAAUAAAUGUUUUAAAUAUAA